GUGUCCGCACAGAGGUCUGCAAGGAGAGAGAGUGUCUUCAUUCUUUCCGCCAUCUUGAUUCUUUCUCACUGACCAAGACUCAGCCGGUAGGUCUGCAGAACGGUGUUACUGGGAAUUUAGUUGUGAGAGAAUGUGUGGAGGAGCCAGCUGGCUUUGGACAGGUCCUGCGGCACAGUCUGUGGCUUCUGAGGGAAAAGGGCCUCGGGGCCGUCAUCCAGCUCCUCCCAGUGGGAAAUAUGAGUGAGCUUCUAAGAGCAAGAUCCCAAUCCUCAGAAAGAGGAAAUGACCAAGAGUCUUCCCAGCCGGUUGGAUCUGUGAUUGUCCAGGAGCCCACUGAGGAAAAACGUCAAGAAGAGGAACCACCAACUGAUAAUCAGGGUAUUGCACCUAGUGGGGAGAUUGAAAAUCAAGCAGUGCCUGCUUUUCAAGGGCCUGACAUGGAAGCUUUUCAACAGGAACUGGCUCUGCUUAAGAUAGAGGAUGAGCCUGGAGAUGGUCCUGAUGUCAGGGAGGGUAUUAUGCCCACUUUUGAUCUCACUAAAGUGCUGGAAGCAGGUGAUGCGCAACCAUAGGUUUCAAGCAAGACAAAUGAAGACUGAAACCAAGAACGUUAUUCUUAAUCUGGAAAUUUGACUGAUAAUAUUCUCUUAAUAAAGUUUUAAGUUUUCUGCAAAGAAUCCUUA